GUUUUGUUAUUUUGCAGCUUUACUGAGUUUAUCAGAUCUGAGAGUUUUUUGGUAGAGUCUUUAGAUUUUUCCAUUUAUAUAAGAUCAUAUUACCUGCAAACAGGGACAAUUUGACUUCUUCCUUUCCAGUUCAGAUGCCCUUUCUUUCUUUCUCUUCCCUAAUUGCCCUGGCUAGGAGGAAUUGUUACGUCUGAUGGGGAUGUAGGAACUUUAAAUUCUAUAUCCUUAACUACUAUUUUAUUUUACCAUGAGCAUGUACAUUUUAUAACAUUAAAAAAACAAAGCAUGGUAGUUUUCAGUAUUAUAGCAACAAUCACUAACUGGCCCUUGGUGAUUUAGAUUUCCUUGGUGAGUUAGAAAUCUAAUGGGAGCAGUUCGGGAAUCUAUAUCCUAACAGGUAUUUCAAGUGGUUCCCAUGGUCAGAUAACUGUGCUAGAGAAAAAGUGAACUGCAUACAAAUAUGCACAAUUAAGAUUAAGUGGAAAUCACUAUAGAAAGGAGAUUAAAAGAAUGAGGCUGCUUUGAAUGAUGCUCAGCUAAGAAAUUAUAAAAUUUGGAGAUGAUAAAUGAUUUUCUAGGAAAUUAUCAAAUCUUAGAGAUGGUAAACCUAGCUUAUUUCAGAUAGAAUGGAAGAAACUGAAAAACAUAUGAGAGCUAUUGCCUCACCUGUAUCACAGGUGAAUUAUUUCAAAUCUUCAUGAAACACCUAAUUCCUAAUCUAUUUAAAGUAUUACAGAGCAGAGAGAAAAAAGUAGUUUGCGAGCUCUGCUGAAAAAGCCAAUAUAACACCAACUCCAAAGCACGGCAAAGAUUAUGUAUGCUUUAAAACUUAAUUGUUCUAAGAUUGUGGUUAAAAUAUUUUAUAAAUAUUAUUUGAAAAAGUAAUACACCACGUCUAAAUGAAAUUCAUUCCAGGAAUCAAAGGAAGGUUCUAUGUUAGGAAAUCUGUUAAUAUACUUACUUAUAUCUUAAUAUACUUAAUCUCUUAUAUCUUAUUGAUAUACUUAUUAAUGGACCAAAGAGAAAAAUUAUGAUCUUUUAGUUUUCUGUGCAAAAUCUGCAUAUGAUAAAAUUAACAUCUUUAUGUGGUUUUUGAAAAUAUAAAACCCAAAACAAGAUUAUUAGAAGAACAACAGAACUAGAACUAGCUUUUCUUUUUCUUUUCUUUUCUUUUUUUUUUGAGAUGGAGUUUCCCUCUUGUUGCCCAGGCUGGAGUGCUAUGGCAUGAUCUCGGCUCACUGCAACCUCUGCCCCCCCGGGUUCAAGUGAUUCUUCUGCCUCAGCCUCCUGAGUAGCUGGGAUUACAAGCAUGUGCCACCACGCCCGGAUCAUGGAGCUUUGUGGUGCAACAAGACUUGGUUAUUUUGGAAGAAGUCAGUUCUACAUUGCUUUGAAACUUGUAGCUGUUGCCCAGUCUGGUUUCCCUUUAAGAGUGGAAAGUAUAAAUACAGUAAAGGACCUUCCUCUGCCAAGAUUUGUUGCUUCAAAGAAUGAACAGGAAUCUCGCCAUGCAGCCUCAUAUUCUUCAGAUUCUGAAAAUCAAGGGUCGUAUUCUGGUGUAAUUCCCCCACCACCUGGCAGGGGGCAAGUGAAAAAGGGAUCCGUAAGCCAUGAUACGGUUCAGCCUCGUACAUCUGCAGAUGCACAGGAACCUGCAUCCCCAGUAGUUUCACCACAGCAAUCCCCACCAACUUCUCCACACACAUGGAGGAAGCACAGCCGUCAUCCCAGCGGUGGGAAUAGUGAGAGGCCUCUCGCGGGACCUGGGCCAUUUUGGUCUCCCUUUGGUGAAGCACAAUCAGGUUCUUCUGCUGGUGAUGCAGUGUGGUCAGGGCAUUCCCCACCUCCACCUCAAGAAAACUGGGUCAGUUUUGCAGAUACUCCACCAACCAGUACUCUUUUAACCAUGCAUCCUGCUUCUGUCCAGGACCAGACAACAGUACGAACUGUAGCAUCAGCUACAACUGCCAUUGAAAUUCGUAGGCAAUCCAGUAGUUAUGAUGAUCCCUGGAAAAUAACAGAUGAACAAAGACAGUAUUAUGUAAAUCAGUUUAAAACCAUUCAGCCUGAUCUAAACGGAUUUAUUCCAGGAUCUGCAGCUAAAGAGUUUUUUACAAAAUCAAAACUUCCUAUUCUUGAACUUUCUCAUAUUUGGGAACUCUCAGACUUUGAUAAAGAUGGUGCAUUGACACUGGAUGAGUUUUGUGCUGCUUUUCAUCUGGUGGUUGCUAGGAAGAAUGGCUAUGAUUUACCAGAAAAACUUCCUGAAAGCUUAAUGCCCAAACUGAUUGAUUUGGAAGAUUCAGCAGAUGUUGGGGAUCAGCCAGGUGAGGUAGGUUAUUCAGGCUCUCCUGCUGAAGCUCCUCCAAGCAAGUCACCAUCGAUGCCAUCACUAAACCAGACAUGGCCUGAGCUGAAUCAGAGCAGUGAGCAGUGGGAGACAUUUAGUGAACGCUCUUCAAGCUCACAAACUCUGACCCAAUUUGAUUCUAACAUUGCACCAGCUGAUCCUGAUACUGCUAUUGUUCAUCCAGUUCCCAUUCGUAUGACUCCAAGCAAAAUCCACAUGCAGGAAAUGGAACUUAAAAGAACUGGCAGCGAUCAUACAAAUCCCACUAGCCCAUUACUUGUGAAACCAUCUGACCUUUUAGAAGAAAAUAAGAUAAAUUCAUCGGUGAAAUUCGCUUCUGGUAAUACUGUAGCAGAUGGUUACAGUAGUUCAGACUCUUUUACUUCUGACCCAGAACAGAUCGGGAGCAAUGUAACUCGUCAAAGGUCUCAUUCAGGAACGUCGCCUGAUAACACUGCACCACCACCUCCCCCUCCAAGGCCACAGCCCUCUCAUUCUAGAUCAUCAUCUUUAGAUAUGAAUCGGACCUUUACAGUCACCACAGGACAACAACAGGCUGGAGUUGUUGCCCAUCCUCCUGCAGUGCCUCCAAGACCACAGCCCUCACAGGCUCCUGGUCCUGCUGUGCAUCGCCCAGUGGAUGCCGAUGGCCUCAUAACUCACACUAGUACCUCACCUCAGCAGAUACCAGAGCAACCAAAUUUUGCAGAUUUCAGUCAGUUUGAAGUAUUUGCUGCAUCAAAUGUAAACGACGAACAAGAUGAUGAAGCCGAGAAACAUCCAGAAGUCCUGCCGGCUGAAAAAGCUUCUGAUCCUGCAAGUUCUCUUCGAGUUGCCAAAACAGAUAGUAAAACUGAAGAAAAGACAGCUGCUAGUGCUCCUGCCAAUGUGAGCAAAGGCACAACACCACUUGCUCCACCACCUAAACCUGUUCGAAGAAGAUUAAAAUCAGAAGAUGAAUUAAGGCCAGAAGUUGAUGAACAUACACAAAAGACGGGUGUCUUAGCUGCUGUUCUUGCAUCACAACCUUCUAUUCCCAGAUCUGUUGGGAAAGAUAAGAAAGCUAUUCAGGCAUCAAUUAGACGUAAUAAGGAAACCAACACCGUUUUGGCCAGAUUGAAUAGCGAAUUGCAGCAACAAUUAAAGGAUGUUCUUGAGGAGAGAAUUUCCCUGGAAGUUCAACUGGAACAACUUCGACCAUUCUCUCACCUAUAAGCCAAUUGCCGUUAACUGUGAACAUACUUGUUUUUAAGUGGUUUUGGGUUCAAAGCCAAUUUGGAGACCUAGACAUUCAGCUCACUGCUUAACUCAACAUUAAAUUUUAUGAUUCUGUUUUGCCCUAUAUGUUCACCGUUGUAUUUAAGUAUCUUUUAUUUUUUAAUUUCGACAAUAAAAAGGUCAGGAUGGCGUUUUCUGGAGGGUAGAUUGUGUUUGUUGGCACACCCACCUUUUCUGUUCCCUAGCAUCUGGGAUAUGCAAUGCUUCUAUGGCUAAUACCACACACCAAUUUAAUUUAUAGAAUGGGCUCCUCAUUUACAUCUCAGUCACAGACUCAGAAAUAAAUUGUCAGUUUGUCCUUUUAUGUUUAAUAUUUUACAUAAAGCAUCUAUUCUAUAAAAAUCUUUAGAAAGAGUUUCCCAUUUAAUUUUGAUUUUAAAGAAUUAUAUUGGAUAAGGUGGUUUUCACCAUAAGCUAAUUUACUCUCUGCAGCCGUCUACAUUCUUCACAAAUCAUGUGGUACAUUGAAGCCUCUUUUACAUGUCAACUUGUGACAAAUACAAACAUGUGAGAUUUUAUAUUUUCCUUGUGGAAAUGUGAUCAACUUCAUCAGCGACUUCGAACUAUUUUAUGAGAUUCAAUAAUUCAGCAGUCAUGUAAACUUAUGAAAUAGGUAUGAGUAAUGGCCUUUCUUAAUUUUUUUAAGUAUUGUUUUAAAACUUCUGAGGAUAUCAGUUAUUCCCAGAAUAAAGGGAAAUUCCUUAGGAUUUCUAGUUUACCUUUAGCCAUCUUGUCACUCAUUCUUUUGCUAUACAGACAAGUUUUUCCUAUUAAUGAGUUUCUGGAGUAUGCCUUAUUCAGGACAAUAUGCUGUUUUAGAUUUUGUUUAAUAUUAAAUGAUAUAUACAUUUCGAUCCAUUGCUAACAGCAGAUAUUCCCUUUAAGAUUUAUUCUGUCUAUAGGAUCAUAGAUUUUAAACUGCAUGGAUAUAUCUUGGCAGAAUCAGAAGUGUGGUUUUACACCAAUAAAACAGCAUAAUAUUUUAACUUUUGUUCAUCUUUUUAACAAGAUUUAAAGUUUUAAGAAAUAGAAGAUUUUGUAUUUUCAUUUCUGAAAGAAAAAAUGUUUAAAUACUAUAGAUUCACAGUCCUAAACUGCACCGAUAGACUUUGUUACUGUAAACAAGAAUUUGAAGAACAAGGGAAACUGACAACCUCAAGCUUCCAAGAUUAAUACAAUUUUUACCUGACAAUAUCUAGGUAAAAAUAUACAUCAGCUGAAGUUUCCAAGUGGCUUUCAGUAUGGCUUUAGUUGUUAAAUAAUAAAUUUAAAGCAUUAAAGGCCCAGGAAACUACUCAACACCUGUUUUUCUGAGUGUCUUUGUUUUCAAAGAAACAUUUUUACUCAGCUGUAUUUCAUUACAAGCAAGUUUUGCUGUUUCCAUUUAGUUUUGUUUUUUAAAAUAUGCUUUUUAAAAAUAGCCUUCUAAUUUAACAAUGUCAAAAAUAUUUGUUAAAGCUUCUUAGAAUUUAGCCUUCCAAUAAAUAACACUUAAAAAUUAUAGAAAA